AUCUUUCCUGGGAGAUGUGAUAGGGAAGAGAAGCCAGAGGGAGACUCUUCAGGUUGGGGGGAGCUAAAGGAGCAGUAGUAAGGAAGCUUGGAGUGGGAGGUGCCUUGGCCCCCGAGGAGGCCUUGGGGAUAGGCCCUCAUUGAUUAUGGCCCAGCCCCUCAGACCCUUCUCCUCUACCGUGCCCUCAGAGGGUCCCUCUGCUGUGGUCGUCCCUGGCUCUUAUACCCCCAGAGAGGCCUGGACCUCUCCCCAUUUUGUCAACUUUCUCUUCCUGACCAGCUGGGCCCCCUGCUCUCCCUGGUUGGCACUGGAUCCAGAAUCUCAGGACUUACGCUGGCCUGGUGUGGGCCCUUGGUUGGACACUUUGCCACACACCUGAGUACCUUUAUGGGGACAAGGGAAGUCCAGGAGCAAGUGGGUGGGCCCAACAUUUCCCUAGUUCUAUUUGAGUCAGGCCCCCUGCUUCUUUGCCCCUCUAGUCGAGAGAGUGGUGGCCUUACUGGAAAAGAGGAGUUGAGGGCCUUGACUUAAUACAGGCCUUGACCUCUUGGACACAGGUCAUCGUUGGUGUUCAUCAGGUUCUAUAAGUGGGUAUGAGGAUCCGAUGUGAGCCUGGAACCCAUCAUCAAGGGUCAGGUUCUGAGUCUCAUGGCACUGUGGUGCUGGGAUUCUCCCCAUCCCACGGGACCAUGGCUGGGACUCUCGAGGCUCUCUCAGGCCAGCUGGUUUGAGGCAACUAUCUCUUUUUUAUAGAGAAGGAGGAAAUGGUGGCAGGCCGGCACAACCUCAGCAUCACUGUAAUUGCUGGUGGCUUUUAUGAGCCAGUCAUGGGGCCGGAGUCCGGCCAACUGUCUGUCCUUCUGUCCCAGUUUGGUGACUUACUCAUGGAGGGAGGGGCGGUUAGGUACUAGAAGCUGUGUUCUAGAAGCUGGACGUCUGACUGUAUUGUGGUCGAUGUCACUCUGUCUAUCCAUGAUCACAGCAGGUAGGAUGGAGCUUAGACUUCAGGAAGAACUUCCCAGUGGGGAAGCUGGGGGGGAGAGAGAUGGCUCUAAUUUUGCAUAGGAAAGGAGGGGAACUCAAAGCACUUUCUUUUCCAGUGGCUCUCCCGAAAGGAAAGGCCUUGACCUUUGGCUUGGUGGGGUCGGUGCUAUUUGGAUCUCGGAAUAUUUAUCUUCUUUUUCCUCUCCCUGCUUAUGGCUGAAAGUAUUCUGAGGCGUUUGUCCUGGAGCUGUGGGAGAAAUAGCCAUUAGGCCCCUUUCCCCCAGUAGUGGGAGCUAGAUAAGGGUCUCAUGUAGACAGGCAUGCCCAAUGCAGUCCACAGCAUUUAGUGGUACACAUGCAGGAAAGUGUGCAACACAUACACACUGGUAUGUAGACACCCACAGAGCAGCUGCUGCACUGCGGGAGGUGGGGGGUAGUGAAUGGCAAAGAUGAUUAAAGGAUUGGAGAGUUGGGAUGGGGUUGAGGGGACCGGAGGCAAGAAGGCGAAGGGCAUAGCAAGAACUUUGAAGAGAGAAGGGCUGACUGGAGCAGGAGGGAUUAAGGUUAGACCACAGAUGGGCAGGCAGAGCCCUGUCUGCAAAAUAAAGAGCAUGGCUUGUGAGUCAAGGAGCCUUGGCUGACUUCCAUCCCUGCCCCUUACCCCUCCCCCACGUGCCCCUCUCUGUGUUCCUGGCACAGCCUGCCUCUGCCCCUCACACUGACCGUGUGUCCCCGGGUCCCUCCUCUUGGGCCCCAGCUUUCCAGAUGUACAGAGUUUCGCCUUUCGGUGAUUAACACCUGGGUGUUUUGGUGGUUUGUCGCUGGUCUCUGUUGCCCUCCCCGCUCACCCUGAUGAGCAAGGCCACUGUGAGGCAUCAAGACUACAUCUAAGCCAUCAGGCAUCUGGGGGUAGAUCCUUGGCCUAGGUGAUCCCCAAGGCCCUCUUCAUCUGACAUUUUCCUUUUCCUGAGGCUGAGGCUACAAGCCUCUCUUUCCUGAGAGCCAAGUUAUGCUUCUGGUUAGUCCUGGCUGGUGUGGAGACAGGGGAAUGCAUUCAUUGAUUCUGCACAGGACCCUGAUAGCCAAGGGGGCGGGAGGCACUUGUGCCUGUCUGACUUCUUUUCUUUCUGCUGUAGGCUGGGAGGGGAGGGACAUGUCCGAAGCUCUGGCCUGUCGCUGGCCACACCCAGGACGGGGCAAUGGAAAGGAGGCCCACGGAGACCUGAGAGGAGGAGGAGAAAUUGAAGGGAAGAGAAAACCAGGAUUCCUCAGCAGAGGGCAGAGAAUCAGCCUUUGGUGGCAAGGAGGCUGUGCAGAAGGUAUCCUGCAGACCAUGAACUGAGCACUGUUCCCAGACCGUUCAUGAGCACAGUGUAAGGUGUGCCGAGACCCACCACCCAGCGAGCCCCUCCCCUCCGUAGCACUGAGGACCCCCGGAGAAGAUGGGGAGGAAAAAGAUUCAGAUCCAGCGAAUCACCGACGAGCGGAACCGACAGGUGACUUUCACCAAGCGGAAGUUUGGCCUGAUGAAGAAGGCGUAUGAGCUGAGCGUGCUAUGUGACUGCGAGAUCGCACUCAUCAUCUUCAACCACUCCAACAAGCUGUUCCAGUACGCCAGCACCGACAUGGACAAGGUGCUGCUCAAGUACACGGAGUACAAUGAGCCACACGAGAGCCGCACCAACGCCGACAUCAUCGAGACCCUGAGGAAGAAGGGCUUCAACGGCUGCGACAGCCCCGAGCCCGACGGGGAGGACUCGCUGGAACAGAGCCCCCUGCUGGAGGACAAGUACCGACGCGCCAGCGAGGAGCUCGACGGGCUCUUCCGGCGCUAUGGGUCAACUGUCCCGGCCCCCAACUUUGCCAUGCCUGUCACGGUGCCCGUGUCCAAUCAGAGCUCACUGCAGUUCAGCAAUCCCAGCGGCUCCCUGGUCACCCCUUCCCUGGUGACAUCAUCCCUCACGGACCCGCGGCUCCUGUCCCCCCAGCAGCCAGCACUACAGAGGAACAGUGUGUCUCCUGGCCUGCCCCAGCGGCCAGCUAGUGCGGGGGCCAUGCUGGGGGGUGACCUGAACAGUGCUAACGGAGCCUGCCCCAGCCCUGUUGGGAAUGGCUACGUCAGUGCUCGGGCUUCCCCUGGCCUCCUCCCUGUGGCCAAUGGCAACAGCCUAAACAAGGUCAUCCCUGCCAAGUCUCCACCCCCACCUACCCACAGCACCCAGCUUGGAGCCCCCAGCCGCAAGCCCGACCUGCGAGUCAUCACUUCCCAGGCAGGAAAGGGGUUAAUGCAUCACUUGACUGAGGACCAUUUAGAUCUGAACAAUGCCCAGCGCCUUGGGGUCUCCCAGUCUACUCAUUCGCUCACCACCCCAGUGGUUUCUGUGGCAACGCCGAGUUUACUCAGCCAGGGCCUCCCCUUCUCUUCCAUGCCCACUGCCUACAACACAGAUUACCAGUUGACCAGUGCAGAGCUCUCCUCCUUACCAGCCUUUAGUUCACCUGGGGGGCUGUCGCUAGGCAAUGUCACUGCCUGGCAACAGCCACAGCAGCCCCAGCAGCCGCAGCAGCCACAGCCUCCACAGCAGCAGCCACCGCAGCCACAGCAGCCACAGCCACAGCAGCCUCAGCAGCCGCAACAGCCACCUCAGCAACAGUCCCACCUGGUCCCUGUAUCUCUCAGCAACCUCAUCCCGGGCAGCCCCCUGCCCCACGUGGGUGCUGCCCUCACAGUCACCACCCACCCCCACAUCAGCAUCAAGUCAGAACCGGUGUCCCCAAGCCGUGAGCGCAGCCCUGCGCCUCCCCCUCCAGCUGUGUUCCCAGCUGCCCGCCCUGAGCCUGGCGAUGGUCUCAGCAGCCCAGCCGGGGGAUCCUAUGAGACGGGAGACCGGGAUGACGGACGGGGGGACUUCGGGCCCACACUGGGCCUGCUGCGCCCAGCCCCAGAGCCUGAGGCUGAGGGCUCAGCUGUGAAGAGGAUGCGGCUUGAUACCUGGACAUUAAAGUGACGAUUCCCACUCCCCUCCUCUCAGCCUCCCUGAUGAAGAGUUGACAAUCUCACCGCCCGCCCUUCCCUGCCCCGGGCUCCUCCCGCUCGACCCCCACUUCCUUUCUUGUGCUUCGUGUCCUGUUGACGGUUACAUUUGUGUAUAAUUAUUAUAUUAUUAUUAUUAUUAUUAUAUUUUUUUUAAUUUGGAUUCUCGCUUUGGAGAGGGGGAUGCUCUCAUCCCCUCUUUCUGUACCCCCCACCAUUUUCACUGGCUGGGGGGCUCUCUUUUUCGCGGGAAGGGGGGACACUUUGCACGUUGUACACAUAUGCUGCAGGAAGGGGGUGGGGGGCCCAAUAAGGCCUUUGGGAAAGGACAGGUGCCGAGCCCUGCAUGUGGAGCCCUCCCACCCCACCCCCAGAUAGAGGGAAAUAACCAAAAAACUACCAAACAACAGAAACCCACACUCUAGACUGAAACCCCAAAGUGGGCUUGAUGGGUGGGUUUGUGUUUCAAGGGGAAAGUGAGGCAGAGGUUCUGAAAAGGGUCUCUGUUUUUGUGUUCAUGUAGCCAUAGGCACAUGGAGCAGAAUACUUAAGCCUGGCCCCCAAAUGCCCCUGCACACACACGUGCCACACCUGCGCUGAUUCUUGUGUGUGCUGCACCCCCAAGGUGUGUGGGUGCUGGCUGAGCUUUGGGCCGGGAAGGCAGCCUGGGAAUCUGAGGCUGGAGACAGGGGUUUGAGGUGGGGGCCUCUCUGGAAGCACAUUUGGAGGGAAAGACAAGAGAGCCAUGAGGAGAGGGCUGAGGAGGGCAGAAGGGCUAGGCAGGGGGCAAAUUGAGCCCCUCCCUUCCCCAGUUUUUCUCUAAGAUAUACAGUGCAAUAGCUCCCCACCCCUCAGUUGACGCCAGCCCUGUAAAGCUGGCCACAGUGUGCAGGGAGAAUGGGGAGAGGGUCUUCAGUGAGGUGGCUGGGGCGAGAGUCGGCCUGGACUUCCCUGGGGUGCUCCAGGCCAGAGCUCUUUCAUUGGGGCGAGUGUGGUGAGGGGACGUCCUUGGUCUUGCACGCACACUACCUGGGGGAGUCAACACUGGGAUGGUCUGUGGGGUGGGAGGGCCUACGGAUGGGUCCGUAGAGGUCCCACCUCCCUCAUUCCUCCUUGGCCCCUCUCCCUAGCUUCUCCUGUUAGCUCCUUCUGCUCCUGACCCCACCUCCUUGCUCUUGGCGCCCCUAUUGUCUCUGGCUACCUCCUUGUCCCACCACCUCCAGGCUGCAUCCCACCUUCCCUCUUGGCUACUGUAAUUGUAAAUAGCGACCUUUGGAAAACGUUAGCGGUGUAACAGUCCAGGAAACUGUUUUUUUUUGUUGUUGUUGUAUUGAUAUGAAAUGAGAUUCUAUUUUUGUCAAAGUAUAUUGUAAUAAUAAUGACUCAAACGGCCCGUACUGUACAGACGAGAUUCUUCUGCUGUUGUUCUUGCUCCCCUCCCCUCCUCUGAGUCCGCCCCUCCCUGCUGCCUCCUCAGUGGGGCAGUGGGCAAGGGGCCCAGGGGCAGCCGAAGCACGGGGUCCUGAGACCUCAGGCAGGAUUGGAGAUCAAACCAGAGGGGGCAGGCCCCCAGCCUGCUCUCUAGGAUCACCCCCCGCCCUAAGGGGCCUGGCCUGGGGUGACGUGGCCAGGCAGACUGUCUGCCCCACUCCUUCACACAAGCCCAGCUCCUCUGCCCAAGGGGUGCGGCGCCCCCUUGGGGUUUCCUCCCAGUUGGAGAGUAGAGUUAAGACAAGGCCCAGUUUUGUGUUAGCCGACCGUCUUUGCCCACCUCUAUGACCCAGCCUCUUGCAGUAUUCCCAUACUUGAUGCAGGGAAGGAACCAGAAGCAGAGGGGCCUCUACGCAGGUACACACGUGUACCUGAGUGUGUUCAUGAGGGCAUCUGGUGUUUAUGUGUCUGAGUGUAGCUUUGUAUUUAUGUGUGUGUGUGUGUGUAUGUCUGAUUGCACGGGUGUACUUUUGUAUUUAUGUGUGUGUGUGGUUGCACGGGUGUGCCUCUGUGUGUCUCUGACCCUGGCUGGGUGUGUGUGCAAAUCUGUGUGACUGGAGCUCUAGGGGCAUCUCUGUGUCUGAGUGUGCCUGGUGUGUGUUUACAAAGGGAGAGUUGGCUGCUCCAGCUCCACAGCCCUGGGACCCCAACUCCUGUCUUCCCUGCUCCUUUCCCUGUGUUCACCCUCAGCUCUGACACAUUGAACUGCAGUUGGGGGGAUUGGCAGUUAGCCCUCUGUGCUUCUCCCUGCAGCCCUACCUCUGCCAAGGUCUCUCCCUCCAGGGACCUCUGCUUCCACCCACAUAUGUCCACUUAGUCACCCACACUUGACACAGUUCCUGGAGUACCCUCUUCCCCCAACCCCAGACCUGCUUUCAGAGCAAAACUCAAGUCCCUCUUCCUCCGUGAAGCUUCUCCCUCAGCUGAGCAGUGAUCACUUACUCACUCUUAACCCCAAUCCGCUGACUGGGUGGGGACAGCACGUCCAGCCUUCCCACCUCUCCUGCAGGCUUCUAGACGGAGUUUCAAAAACUGAUGAGCCUCGAUCCAGGGCUUGAAAGAAGCCAGGGUGUAAUCUUGUUCAUGCAUGCGUCCCCAGAGCCUCGCCCAGUGCCUGGCACAUAGUAGGCACUCAAUAAAUGCUGAAUGGGUGAAUAGUUGAAUGAUAGGUGCUCAAUAAAUGAAUGAAUGGCCUUCCCUUCUCAGGCUAUUCCCACCAUUAGUCUGCCCACCUUUCUAGGCUGGGCUUGGCCACCAUUAAACACGGGGUGGGGGUGAGGGCCCCUGCAAUUCACGGUGCAAUAUUCACCAGUUUUGCCCUCUGCCUCAUAAAGGCAAACCUGGCUUUUGAUUACCAUGUGUGGAUGUUUCAGUGUCCUUUCUUCUCUGUCCCUGGGGAUGGGGUGGUCUGUGAAUAUGUGACAUUUCUGCAGUUCAGUAUCCGAAGGUUUCUCUUGGGGGUAGGGGCUCCUGGGCGGCCAGAUGAAUGGGUCCCUGGGAACCCAGACCUCAGAUGAGGACUUAAUGUCUUCUUCCUCUCAAGCCAAAUUCGCCUCCACCCACUCCCUCUGAAGAACUGGGCAUUUGCCAAAGUAACCACUGGAGUCAUCUAAUGGCCCUCCCCCUCCCCAGGUUUCCCACAGCUUUCAGGGACAGUGGGCAAGAGGACACCCCCCCCCACCACCUCAGUGGAACACACCAUUCUCCCCCCCUCAACAGCACACUCAGUGCAGCAAGACUGACCCCUGACCCCCUCCCAGCCCUCCCUACCUUGGACAGGAAGGAAGUAAUGCACCUUCUCUUGCUGAUUAUUUAUUUGUUUGGAGAGACAGAAAUGUAAAAGUGUAUCUAGAAAUAUCUAUAUCUCUAUAUAUUUUUAACUGACUCUUUGGAAUCCCCUGGGGUGGGGUGAGGGGUAAGUUUAGGCUUUCGCGGAGGGGAGGAGACAUGGAGCCUGGGAACUCCUUGUUCUCCCCUCUGCUGCCUCUCCCCACCCCUUAAAGCAGUUGGUAGAAGGAAUGGUAUUUGUAUGGGGGGAGGGAGGCUGGAAUGGAGAAUCUGGAUUCUCUCCUCUUCCCCAUUCUCCAGAGGGAGGGAGGUGGUGAGGAAGAGGAAGGGAGGGGCAGGAUGGGCCAUGGAGGUGCCCCACCCCCACACCUGACAAUCACCCACACUCCUGGGGCUCUUCCUGGGUCCUGGGGCAGGGCGAGUCCAAGUGUGAGGCUGUUGAUUUGUUUUCAAUAUUUCUUUUCGUGCUGUAUGGUGAUGCUUUCUUAGUAUUCUACACAAUAAGAAAAGACAAAGUCCUCGAGAUUCUUAUGAGUUUUGUUUGAAAACUCUUUCACUAUAUUUGUUGUAAAGAGGUUUACUAUUAAAAGAAAAAGAAUACACGUUUCUGAUA